AGUUCAGUAAGGUAGAGCUUUGGCCGAGGACGAGGGGAAGAUGUCACGCAAGAUAGAAGGCUUUUUGUUAUUACUUCUCUUUGGCUAUGAAGCCACAUUGGGAUUAUCGUCUACCGAGGAUGAAGGCGAGGACCCCUGGUACCAAAAAGCAUGCAAGUGCGAUUGCCAAGGAGGACCCAAUGCUCUGUGGUCUGCAGGUGCCACCUCCUUGGACUGUAUACCAGAAUGCCCAUAUCACAAGCCUCUGGGUUUCGAGUCAGGGGAGGUCACACCGGACCAGAUCACCUGCUCUAACCCGGAGCAGUAUGUGGGCUGGUAUUCUUCGUGGACUGCAAACAAGGCCCGGCUCAACAGUCAAGGCUUUGGGUGUGCCUGGCUCUCCAAGUUCCAGGACAGUAGCCAGUGGUUACAGAUAGAUCUGAAGGAGAUCAAAGUGAUUUCAGGGAUCCUCACCCAGGGGCGCUGUGACAUCGAUGAGUGGAUGACCAAGUACAGCGUGCAGUACAGGACCGAUGAGCGCCUGAACUGGAUUUACUACAAGGACCAGACUGGAAACAACCGGGUCUUCUAUGGCAACUCGGACCGCACCUCCACGGUUCAGAACCUGCUGCGGCCCCCCAUCAUCUCCCGCUUCAUCCGCCUCAUCCCGCUGGGCUGGCACGUCCGCAUUGCCAUCCGGAUGGAGCUGCUGGAGUGCGUCAGCAAGUGUGCCUGAUGCCUGCCUCAGCUCGGCGCCUGCCAGGGGGUGACUGGCACAGAGCGGGCCGUAGGGGACCCCCUCACACACCACCGAGAUGGACAGGGCUAUAUUUCGCAAAGCAAUUGUAACUGCAGUGCUGGGUAGAUAAUUUUUUUUUUUUUAAGAUAUAGCUUUCUGAUUUCAAUGAAAUAAAAAUGAACUUAUUCCCCACUCAGGGCCAGAGAAAGUCAGAACAAAGAAAAUGUCCCCGAAACGAAUUUUCUUACAAAAGCCUAAGUAGCAGGGGUAAUUUUCUGCUCAUUUUUUGUCUCAGUGAUACUGUGAAAGGUGCAGUCUCAGGGGAACACAAAGCAGCCCUGAUAAUUUGAAAAUUCAUUUGCUUUACCACAUUCAAGACAGAAACAUACAGUUUCCUAAAGCCUGGCUUUGAAUGCAGAAGGGAGCAGCUCCUCCUAGUUAAGUUUCCACUAAAUCAUCGCCAAAGAGGACUUCAGAGCCCUGGGGAGGCAGCUGAGGGUCUCAAGGGUGACUGGGUGGCAGGGAUGAGUGCGGUGGGUGAGAAUCCCGGUGCCCUGAGAGGCUAUACGUGACAAAUGACCAAAAGCCCAAGGUAGGGGAGUUUCCUCUGCUCACAGUUCUUACCUUCAAGGCGGAUCUGGGCUUCCACCCUCAUGAACACAGGGAUUGGGGAGGGACCAGAGCGCCCAAUACACACAGCUCCAUUAUGCAAUCCAUUCCAGCAAAUUCCCCGUGUCUGUGGUCACCAUUUAGGUGAUCAUACAGGACAGGCUGCACAUCUCAGUAUAUGUAGGGACCCCAAAUGACCACAACACAGUACAAUUGCCCUUUACCUAGGGCUACCAUUUCCUAGCAAACCAAACAUAGUUCGAGAACAGCUGGCCCAGGAGCUACCACUGGCUACUCAGAGGAGGCUCAUUAGCUGGCUACAUGCUUCGCAGGAAGUGGGAAGGACUCACAUCAUAAAAAGGACCAUGUAGCUUUUUCCCUGAAAGCUUCUCACCCUCCACCCUCUGCCUUGCAAUACGCAAACUGCGCCUGCUCCUGAAAAGCUCUCUGGGAAGGAAUGGGCCUGGCUUUCCGUUCCUGGAGGCGGCGCCUUAGAUUGGGAGGCCUCAUUGGCCACUUAGAGCGCAGCCUGAGUUUCCAGGCCCCUUCCUGGGAGAGGCUGUUAACACGGGGGAGGGGCAGGAGAGGGAUAUGGAGAGCAGGUGGUGGAAUCAGAGGACGAGGCUGCUCUAAAGACUGUUCUGGCCCCAGACACAGGGUAGUCUUUGCUAGCAGCUCAUUUCCGAGUUACUUUUCAUUUUCAAAUGCCAAGGCAAGUGACUAGACUCGCGCUAAUACAGUGCUGGACAACACAUUCACCUUUUCUGUGAACAGGCAGCCUUCUAAAAGCCCCAAACAUCCUUCUUGAUGCUUUGGGGGCUCAAUUAUUUUAUAUCCAACCCAGCAUCUUUCUAGUCCCUAUGCUGUAUGCUUGAACUUCGGAAAAUGCUUUUCCCCGCCCAAUCUUCUCUCAAAUAUAAACACAUCACACAGGGUGUUGGGGGUGGGGGGGGGGGGUGGGGGGACUUAUCCCUGGCCUUAGGACACAGGACAAAUCUAUUUUGGAUAGAAAUGCCUGAACAGAGACCCUUAUUUGGAAAGGUGAAUUAACUUUGGUCACGACAUGGACUGUCAGACAAAAUGGCAGUAUCCUAAGAGUUAAGGCACAUCAAACACAGGAGUCGAGAGAGUGCAGUUCAGGGAAAAAGGAGAGGAGGAAACAGUGAGGCAGGGAGAAAGGCUUUCCAAAUAAGAGUUCAUGUUGGAAACUUUUGUCACGGCUUUAUUGAGAUUAAGUUCACAUACAAUUUGUAUCCAUUUAAAGUGUACAAUUUGAUGACUUUUGGUAUAUUCAGAGUUGUGCAACCAUUAUCACUAGAUCAAUUUUAGAAAGUUUAUCACCCCAAAGAGAAAUCCUGCACCCAUCAGCCAACACUCCCCAACCCAUCGGCCACCCCAAGCCCUCUGCAACCACGAAUCGACUGUCUCUGUAGAUUGGCCUUCUGGACGUUCUACAUAAAUGAAAUCAUAUAGUAUGUGGUAUUUCGUGACUGGCUUCUUUCACUUAGCAUAGUGUUUUAAAGUUCAUCCACGUUAUAACAUGUGUAUCACUAUGUCACUUGUCACUCCUUUUUAUUGCUGAACAUCAUUGUUCAGUAUCAUGUCAAGAGCACAUUGUUAUUUAUCCAUUCAUCCAUUGAUGGAUAUUUGGGUUUCCACUCUUUAGCUAUUAUGAAUAAUGCUGCUAUGAACAUUUGUGUAUAA